UUUUUUUUAAAUGACCUUGACAGUUUUCAGUUCACCAGUCAGAUAUUUUGUAGAAUGUUGCUCAGUUGAGAUUCGUCUGUUGUUUUUCUCAUGGUUAUGCUGGGGUUAGGAGUUUCAGGGAGGGAGAUCACAGAGGCAGCAGGCCAUUUUCAUCACAUCAUUUCAGAGGUAUAUACAGUCAACAUGACUCAUCAGUGUUGAUGUUGACCUUAGUCACUCUGCUGGGGUCGUGUUUGCCCAGCUUCACCACUGCAGAGUUCCUCCUUCUUACCUGUUUCUGUGCUUCCCUCUUGGGAAGGCAGCCCACGCUUCAGGAGUGGGAAGUUAUGCCUACCUCCUUGAGGGCAGAAUAUCUAUGUAGAUGAUUUGGAGUUCUGUACAGGAGCUGUAUCUAUCUCCUCCAUUUCUUUAUUCAACAUUUAUAUCUGUAUAUACUCAUGAAUAUACCCUGGGUUAUAAUCCAAUGCUACUUUAUUUAUUGCUCAGAUUGUUCUAGCUUUUGUCGUUGGGAGCUAUUUCAGUUGGUUCCUGUGCCCCCUUGCCAUAUCCCUAUCAUCGUGGGUUUAUAUCUUAAUUUUUUAAAUAUCUGCAUGGUAUUCCAUUGUAAGAAUGUACUCUACUAUAAUUUAACCAAUCCCUUAUUGAUGGCAAUUGAGGUAUCAAAUCAGUUGUAAACAAUACUGUGAUAAGCAGUCUUCAGAAGACAUUUAUGAAAAUUGUCGAUCAUGUAUUCAGAAAGGUCUGCCCAUUUUACUUUCUUUUUUUUUUUUUUUUUUUUUUUUGAGACAGAGUCUUGCUCUGUUGCCCAGGCUGGAGUGCAGUGGUGCGAUCUCAGCUCAUCGCAACCUCCACCUCCCAGGUGUGAGCAAUUCUCCUGCCUCAGCCUCUUGAGUAGCUGGGAUUACAGGUGCUCUCCACCAUGCCCAGCUAAUUUUUGUAUUUGUGGUACAGACGGGGUUUCACCAUGUUGGUCAGGCUGGUCUCAAACUCCCAACCUCAAGUGAUCCACCCACCUCGGUCUCCCAAAGUGCUGGGAUUACAGGGGUGAGCCACCGUGCCCAGCCAUUUUACAUUUCAUGUGAUAUGUGACUCUUAAUAAUACGUAAGCAGAUUUCAGAGGCGUGAGCAUUCUCACGAAAAAUAGAGGUGUAUCUGUCACCAGAGUUGCCUCCCUUCCUUUUUCUGUAUUUCCUUUAGUGAGGGAUGAUGGUGGGUGUGGCACCAGCAGUCCUAAAGAGCUGCUUUGAGAUCACACUUGUCUGAGACACCUGUGCCUUUUCAAUAUAGAGUCAGCUACUGUAGACAGCUAACAAAAGAUGAACUAAAACUCAAUUCAGAAAAAAACAAAACAGCAUUCUCAGAGUAAAAAUAUUAGACCUGGAAGCAACCUUAGAAAUCAUCAUGCUUUAGCAGUGGAUUUUAGAAAUAGGAAACUUUUUAUUAGGUGAGAUGAUUUGCCUGGGAUUAUGCAGUAGCAAAAGCAUUUAAGAAUCUGGAUUUCUGCCUCAGUCUCAGAAUUUCUUGUUACAUGGGUAUAUUUUAUUUUUAUUUUUAUUUAUUUAUUUAUUUAUUUAUUUGAGAUGGAGUUUUGCUCUUGUUGCUUAAGCUGGAGUGCAAUGGCACAGUCUUGGCUCACUGUAACCUCUGCCUCCCGGGUUCAAGCGAUUCUCCUGCCUCAGCCUCCCAAGUAGCUGGGAUUACAGGCGCUCGCCACCACAACUGGCUCAUUUUUGUGUUUUUAGUAGAGACAGGGUUUCACCAUGUUGGCAAGGCUGGUCUCGAACUCCUGACCUUGUGAUCUGCCCGACUCGGCCUCCUAAAAUGCUGGGAUUACAGGGGUGAGCCACAGCGCCCAGCCUGCAUGGGUAUAUUUUAUAUCUCAUGCAAGGAUAUGCACAAUUUUUUAUGUUGGAAAUUUUUAAGCUUAAAGAAGACAAAAUAGUGUAAUUAAUCAUGUCCCCACCACCCAGCUUUAUAAAUUUGUGGCCAAUCGUGUUAAAACUUCUACCCACUCCCCCCACCACCAUGUUAUUUUGAAGUAAAUCCCACAUAUUAAAUCACUAUAAAUAUUUCAGUAUAUUCAAAAGGAAAAAACUUUUUUCAAAGCAUAACCAUAAUACCAUUUUCAUAUCUUAAAAGCCUUUCUAUUUAAGAAUAUUUAGUUGUAAAAAUUUCCAGAAGUUGUGUUUAUCAUGAAUUAAAAUGUGGCUUUAGUGAAAAUACAGUUCCUUGGUAUACUCUCCCAGCAAUUAGGGAGAGAUUCUGUCCACCAGCAGAAUGGCCUGGGUUACAGCUUUUAUCAAAAUCUGCUGUCUGAGGGUCUUAGUUGGAAGAAAUAAUCUCCUAUUUGAGUUCUUCGAGGCCGAAAGAUUGAUAAUGACUGUAUGGCCGAUCUCUAACUAUAUAUUGUUGCUUUUUUACCUUAAUUAACUCUUAAGCUUUGUACGUGAGGAAGAAAUUCCAAGGACAUAUCACAAGAAGAAUUAUUUUUCAGAUUUCGCCACUAGCCGAAGCCACGGAUGGGAAUGUGGUGGUGGAGCUGUUCCACUCAGAUCUUCUGUGAGGGAUUUCUGAAGGAGGAGACAUCACAGCUUUCCCAGAUCGGGAGGAAAAAUAUGGAAUGUGUUUUACCGCUGACUGAACACAACCAAAUGAACUGUCCUGACAGUAGUUUGCAAACCAGCAGCUAGCAGUUUGUCCAGCCUCUAACAUUGUCCAGCACUUUCCAGAGCAAACUCACUGUUUACAAGAACUCUUGGCCUUACGAAGUUUAUAACCUCAAGCUUUGUUUAUUUAAAAUAUUCCUGCAAAAGAAAAGUACCCGGCACCCACUUUCCAAAAUGGCCAUGGAUGAGUAUUUGUGGAUGGUCAUUUUGGGUUUCAUCAUAGCUUUCAUCUUGGCCUUUUCUGUUGGUGCAAACGAUGUUGCCAACUCCUUUGGUACAGCCGUGGGCUCUGGUGUGGUGACCUUGAGGCAGGCAUGCAUUUUAGCUUCAAUAUUUGAAACCACCGGCUCCGUGUUACUAGGCGCCAAAGUAGGAGAAACCAUUCGCAAAGGUAUCAUUGACGUGAACCUGUACAACGAGACGGUGGAGACUCUCAUGGCUGGGGAAGUUAGUGCCAUGGUUGUUGCUUCUUGGUUUAUAUCUCCACUGUUGUCUGGUUUCAUGUCUGGCCUGCUGUUUGUACUCAUCAGAAUUUUCAUCUUAAAAAAGGAAGACCCUGUUCCCAAUGGCCUCCGGGCACUCCCAGUAUUCUAUGCUGCUACCAUAGCAAUCAAUGUCUUUUCCAUCAUGUACACAGGAGCACCAGUGCUCGGCCUUGUUCUCCCCAUGUGGGCCAUAGCCCUCAUUUCCUUUGGUGUCGCCCUCCUGUUCGCUUUUUUUGUGUGGCUCUUCGUGUGUCCGUGGAUGCGGAGGAAAAUAACAGGCAAAUUACAAAAAGAAGGUGCUUUAUCACGAGUAUCUGACGAAAGCCUCAGUAAGGUUCAGGAAGCAGAGUCCCCAGUAUUUAAAGAGCUACCAGGUGCCAAGGCUAAUGAUGACAGCACCAUCCCGCUCACGGGAGCAGCAGGGGAGACACUGGGGACCUCGGAAGGCACUUCUGCGGGCAGCCACCCUCGGGCUGCAUACGGAAGAGCACUGUCCAUGACCCAUGGCUCUGUGAAAUCGCCCAUCUCCAACGGCACCUUCGGCUUCGACGGCCACACCAGGAGCGACGGUCAUGUGUACCACACCGUGCACAAAGACUCGGGGCUCUACAAAGAUCUGCUGCACAAAAUCCACAUCGACAGGGGCCCCGAGGAGAAGCCAGCCCAGGAAAGCAACUACCGGCUGCUGCGCCGAAACAACAGUUACACCUGCUACACCGCAGCCAUUUGUGGGCUGCCAGUGCACGCCACCUUUCGAGCUGCGGACUCAUCGGCCCCAGAGGACAGUGAGAAGCUGGUGGGCGACACCGUGUCCUACUCCAAGAAGAGGCUGCGCUACGACAGCUACUCGAGCUACUGUAACGCGGUGGCAGAGGCGGAGAUCGAGGCGGAGGAGGGCGGCGUGGAGAUGAAGCUGGCGUCGGAGCUGGCCGACCCUGACCAGCCGCGAGAGGACCCUGCAGAGGAGGAGAAGGAGGAGAAGGACGCACCCGAGGUUCACCUCCUGUUCCAUUUCCUGCAGGUCCUCACCGCCUGUUUCGGGUCCUUUGCUCACGGCGGCAAUGACGUGAGUAAUGCCAUCGGUCCCCUGGUAGCCUUGUGGCUGAUUUACAAACAAGGCGGGGUAACGCAAGAAGCAGCUACACCCGUCUGGCUGCUGUUUUAUGGAGGAGUUGGAAUCUGCACAGGCCUCUGGGUCUGGGGGAGAAGAGUGAUCCAGACCAUGGGGAAGGACCUCACUCCCAUCACGCCGUCCAGCGGCUUCACGAUCGAGCUGGCCUCAGCCUUCACAGUGGUGAUCGCCUCCAACAUCGGGCUUCCAGUCAGCACCACGCACUGUAAGGUGGGCUCGGUGGUGGCCGUGGGCUGGAUCCGCUCCCGCAAGGCUGUGGACUGGCGCCUCUUUCGGAACAUCUUCGUGGCCUGGUUCGUGACCGUCCCUGUGGCUGGGCUGUUCAGCGCUGCUGUCAUGGCUCUUCUCAUGUAUGGGAUCCUUCCAUAUGUGUGAUUUGUCUUCUUCCAGCUGCAAACAGCUAAAGGGAUGGUCUGGUGUUGGCGUGUGGGAGACAUGUGUGCUCGUGCCGCACAUACACAUCCUGGCCGUGCACGGCUCUCUCAUGACCAGCUCUCUGCCUCCCUUCCAGGAGGCUCCAUCCCACACUGUUCACCCAGGCUGCGGAGACUCACCUUCCCGAGCUAACUUAACUACUGUACAUAAUAAUAUGUAUUAAACUGGUAUCGUGGUGAUAUAAUGUGGUGCAGUUACUUAUAUAUUAAAUAUCUAUUGUAUCCAUAGAAUAGGCAGCAUUAUUUCAAACAUAUUCAAGUUGGGAGUGGAGAUCAUUGCCUAGAAGUCAAUAUUCAAUAAAUCUUGUACAUAACUAUUUCGAUGGCAAAUGUUAAGCCUUCUAAAAGGAAAGUGUAGAUUGGAAAAUGAUUUUUUUUCCAAAUGAUGUUUUUGCCUUCUAAUAUACUGUAAGGUAAUGAGCUUCAGAACAGGCAACCUGACCCUGCAGAGGUCGCGUGCUGUGGGAUGACAGCGGGACGGGAGCUCACAAGUGCUUUCACUGAAGAUUUGUUCAUAUACUGUGUAUUGAUUGUUGUGUAAUAUAUCAUCAUUGCUUUUGUAAAUACGUAAAACUGUAAUUUUUUAAUGGUGUGCUUCCCUUAUACUUUUUUGAUCAGAGAAUUUUGGAAAGUACCAAAGAAGCAGGGGAAUCAUUGGCCAGUGUUACGUUUUCACAUUGUCUGUCUCCCACCCUCACUGAUCACGCCUGCCCCAGAGCAGUGUGUGGCGGUGACACCGUCACCCAGCAUGCGCCACGCCGUGGCUCCCACCAGCAGUGCCACCGCCACCACACCCCAGAUCCCACCCACCUUGCAGUGGCCUUUCCUUGUCAUCAGAGUAGAGAAUGCACAGGUGUUGGUGAGGGCGUGUGGCUGAGCACUACAUGUCAAGUCCAGAGUCAGUUUCUAUCCCAAUUCUCCCUGCAGCCUGAAGAACGGAUCCUUGUCUCCAAUGUCAGCACAAAGGAGGCUUUUUCUGUGCUUUGACAUUCUAGCACUUCAGGGAUGAGAGGGAGGGAGAAUCCUGGAUGCUGGAUGGAGUAUUUCUCUGAGGCCCACACAAAGCUGGACACCCCCAGGCUCUACUCCAUCCCAUUGGAGUCUCUUCUUUUUUUGAUAGCGGGAGGGAGGAAGUACGACUAAUGUUGGAGCCUGAAACUAUGGAAAUGCUGCUAAAAUUUUUAUAUUGACAAACAUUUUCUUGGUACUUCAUUGUCAUUUUUCAUUAAUCAACCAUAUUAAAUUUAUAAUAAAAAAUGCCCCUCAGAA